GCCUCUUGCCGCCGCAGCAGCAGCAGUACCGGCAUCCUCGGCUCGCGCUCGCUACCUUCGCCCGCUCCGCGCAAUCUGGGUGCCGCCGGGGAGCCCAGCCCAGCGCCGGACGCGUAGUCAAUCCGUUGCCCAGCGUUGGCCAGCGGCUGCCGCUUGUCCAGGGGGAGAAUCAGCACGAUCCUGGUCUGGGGGUGGAACAGGGGCGUGAGGCGGGAGAGCGCGCUAGGGCCGAGCCCACGACCCGGGGCCGCUCCGCGCUUCUCCUGGGACCCUCGUCCACCCGGGUCCUGUCGUCCACCCGGGUCCUGUCAUCCUCUCGUGCACAGGGCUGGAGGGGACCCCUGUCCAAUUCAGGCCGCGGGGAAGCCCGCCCUUCCCUGCGUGGCGCCCCGGACUCCGCCUCCUUUCUGGAAACCCUCAUCCAUCCCAGGCUGACUUCCUGAGACCAGCUCCGUCUAAGUUUAUGAGAUCCCUUCCAGGCCCUAUGUCAGGGGCUUUCAGCACCUCCCACCCCCGCCUGGUCCAGGGCUUCUGCUCAUUUGAGAGGGAGACAGGGAAGUUCUGAGCCUAGGAGCUGAAGAGAGGACACUAGGGAAUUCCCCCUGCCUCUAGCUCCAGUAGUACCAACUAGAACUGAUUCUCCGUGUUGGGAUCUCCACCCGUUCGUCCAGGGUUGGGAGAGAAUCCCACUCAUGCUCACCCCCCGGGGCUCUCAAGUCUCAUCCACUUUCUGGUUCUGGAAUCUCUGCCCUCCCUUCUGGGCUUUUUUUGUUUAAGACUGAGUCAAACAGGGUCUUGCUGUGUCCUACAGGCUGGAGCAGUGGUGCUGUCAACGGCUCACUGCAUCCCUGACCUCCUGGGCUCACGUAGUCCACCUCAGUCUUCUGAGUAGCUGGGACUGCGGGCAUUCACCACCACAACCAGCUAAGUUUUAAUUUUUGUAGAGAUGGGGCCUCCCUAUGUUGCCCAGGCCAAUCUCAAACUCCUGGGCUGAAGUUAUCCACCCACCUUGGCCUACCAACGUGUUGGGAUUACAGGCGUGAGCCACCUUGAAAGGACCCCCAUCCACACCCAUAUGGGCUCCUGGGAUCCUCAUCCUUGGGAGAGAUUUUCGAAUUCCUCCCUCACCCCCUAGGACUUCUGCAUACAAGGCCUAGACUCCCAGCAUCCCUUCCCACCCACUUGUCCAGCUUUCUCUGCCCCCCAGCUGCCUCCCCAGCCCUGCUCCCCAUCCCCCGCCCUCACAGCCGGCUUCUUCCGAGUGAGGUGGUUGAGGAACGAUUUCCACCAGGCCUUGUCCAUGUCAGCCGGCCUCUCCUUGCGGGCCUGCUUGGGUGCUUUGGUCCUUUUGUGGGAACUAUAGUUUCCCAUGGCAGGGCUGGUCACCACUGGGGACGAUGGCCCACACUCCGUCUGCUCUGCCCCCUGGGCCCUGGCAACAUUGUGACCUCACGGGCUGACCUCACCAAUUGCAGGCUCUGAGCACCGCCUUCCAGGGCCCACAGGAGUACGAGAGGGCCUCCAAAGUGGACCAGUUUGUGACGCGCUUCCUGCUGCGGGAGACGGUGAGCCAGCUGCAAGCCCUUCAGAGCUCGCUGGAGGGGGCGUCAGAUACCCUGGAGGCCCAGGCCCAUGGCUGGCGUCCUCGGCCCUGUGAGCCUCACUUCCUCUAGGUCAGAUGCAGAGAGCGUGGAGGCGCAGAGCAGGCUCUGCGGCAGCCGGCGGGCAGGACGCCGAGCCCUGAGGAGUGUCAGCCGGUCAUCCACCUGGUCCCCCGGCUCUUCUGACACAGGGCGCAGCUCAGAGGCCGAGAUGCAGUGGCGGCUCCAGGUGAACCGCCUCCAGGAGCUCAUCGACCAGCUCGAGUGCAAGGCCCCCCGGCUGGAACCCCUGCGUGAAGAGGACCUGGCCAAGGGGCCUGACUUGCACAUCCUCAUGGCCCAGAGGCAGGUCCAGGUGGCAGAGGAAGGCCUGCAGGACUUCCACCGAGCCCUGCGCUGCUAUGUGGACUUCACAGGGGCCCAGAGCCAUUGUCUGCAUGUGUCCGCCCAGAAGAUGCUGGACGGUGCCUCCUUCACCCUGUAUGAGUUCUGGCAGGAUGAGGCCUCCUGGAGAAGGCACCAGCAGUCGCCUGGCAGCAAGGCCUUCCAGCGCAUCCUCAUCGACCACCUGCGGGCCCCGGACACCCUCACCACUGUGUUCUUCCCAGCCUCCUGGUGGAUAAUGAAUAACAACUGAGCCAGACCUGCACACGCCGAGGGCCCCGGGACCCUGCCUGCCUCCCUCUGGAGCCUUCUGGACUGGCCAGCCCAGCGCAAAGACCAGGACUUGUCUCCUCCUGGACUUGGGCCUGGUGGAAGGGCUCUCAGCCCAGGGAUCAGGGACUGGGCUGCUUGCUUUCUAUUUAUUAUUGAUUUAUUUAUCCCUGUAUUUUAUUGUUUGUCACUUCAGCCUCCAAGCUACUUUGGCUUCUGCCUGGCUCAGGAGACCUGGAUUCUGGUCCCUGCUGUCCCUGCCUGGCUGAGCGACCCAGGGCAGGUCCCGUCCCUGUCUGGGUGGGCCUCAGGCCAUCUGGCCGCCUAGCGAGGGUCCUGCUUUCUUCCUGCUGUCUUGGGACCAGGCUUCUGCUCCUCCUCAGCCAGCGGCAGAAGCAGGGCUGAUGCUCAGGGACCCCCCAACCCUCAAACCUUGCCUCCGAGGCUGGGCCUGAGCUGGGUGCCCCGUCGCCCUCCCAGGCCACUAGGCUCUGACUCUUCCAGCACCCAUGGAUGUGCCAGAGGCCUCUGGGUUGGUUUGCAUGUCAUUUGCAUAUCGUUUGCAUGCCCUCAUCCCACCCAUUCUCAGGGCAGUAUGGGAAGCCCCAAGGUGACCUGGCCAAGUAGCAAUAAUUUGGGUCCAGGGUCACCUAUUGCCCCCAGAGGCCUCUGAACCCCAGGCUGGGACCCCAGCACAGAGGCAAUAAAGGCAGUGGUCCCUUCCA